GGGUUUGUUGACAGCGGAGGCGGCGGCGGCUGCAGGCUCCGAGCCGUAGGAGCCGGAUCGGGGGAGGGGCCGGGCCCAGGAGCCUCAGCCCCGCCGGCAGCCCUAAGGGCAAGGUAACCGCCACGGGGUCCCCGUCGCGACCCCCUCCCUCCCGGAGCUCCCGUCCCCGGGAUCCCAAGCUCCGCCCCGCCGACCCCCGUCUCCCCUGGACCCCGGCUCUAGCCUGACGAGAUCCCCAACCUCCUGAGGUGCUCUGGCCCCGGAUUCUCCCGGGCUGCAUUCUCUGCUCCUCCUCGCCUGCGAAGCAUCACGUCCGCUUCCCGACGCUGAGGGCAGCCCCGUCCAGGGUAGGUCCCGGACCCCGGGCCAAGGGACGUACCUGCGUCCUCCUCCUUCGCCUCCUGCCUACGGGGCCUAAGCAUCGCCGCUGCAACCACUCUCUGAGGUCCAUCUCCGCCAGUGGUGGGAGGGUUCCUUUCUCUAUCCCUGCCGCCAGGUCUGAGAAUCGUGUCUUUAAAACUGAGCUCCCUUCCUCCAGAAAGAAAAUGACGCUCUGUCGUUUGCCCCUACAAGAUGGGGGAUCGGUGUAGGGCUGAAAGGGCCACCCUCUGCCCCUCCUACCUGUUGGAUGAGCUUAAGUUCCCCCAGAGAAGUGCUUAGAAGCUCAAGGACGACUUGGAUUCUGGAUCAGCUCCCAAAAGGGAUGACACAAAGUAUAGGGAAAUCCAACAGGGUGAGGUUGCAACCGGAGGGCCAAGGGAGCCCGACAGGCAGUGGCUCUGCCAAUGAUCCUGUGAGUAUUCAGGAAUCACUGUUGCCCCUGGGGAUCCUUGUCCUGGAGUGGCCCACCUGCUUGCCCCCAGCAUGGCGUCCGACACUCCCGAGUCGCUGAUGGCCCUCUGUACUGACUUCUGCUUGCGCAACCUGGAUGGCACCCUGGGCUACCUGCUGGACAAGGAGACCCUGCGGCUACAUCCGGACAUCUUCUUGCCCAGCGAGAUCUGUGACCGGCUCGUCAAUGAGUAUGUGGAGCUGGUGAACGCUGCCUGUAACUUCGAGCCACACGAGAGCUUCUUCAGCCUCUUUUCGGACCCCCGCAGCACCCGCCUCACGCGGAUCCACCUCCGUGAGGACCUGGUGCAGGACCAGGACCUGGAGGCCAUCCGCAAGCAGGACCUGGUGGAGCUGUACCUGACUAACUGCGAGAAGCUGUCCGCCAAGAGCCUGCAGACACUGAGGAGCUUCAGCCACACCCUGGUGUCCUUGAGCCUCUUCGGCUGUACAAACAUUUUCUAUGAGGAGGAGAACCCAGGGGGCUGUGAAGAUGAGUACCUCGUCAACCCCACCUGCCAGGUGCUGGUUAAGGAUUUCACCUUCGAGGGCUUCAGCCGCCUCCGCUUCCUCAACUUGGGCCGCAUGAUUGAUUGGGUCCCUGUGGAGUCCCUGCUGCGGCCGCUUAACUCCCUGGCUGCCUUGGACCUCUCAGGCAUUCAGACGAGCGACGCCGCCUUCCUCACCCAGUGGAAAGACAGCCUGGUGUCCCUCGUCCUCUACAACAUGGACCUGUCCGACGACCACAUCCGGGUCAUCGUGCAGCUGCACAAGCUGCGACACCUGGACAUCUCCCGAGACCGCCUCUCCAGCUACUACAAGUUCAAGCUGACUCGGGAGGUGCUGAGCCUCUUUGUGCAGAAGCUGGGGAACCUAAUGUCCCUGGACAUCUCUGGCCACAUGAUCCUAGAGAACUGCAGCAUCUCCAAGAUGGAAGAGGAAGCGGGGCAGACCAGCAUUGAGCCUUCCAAGAGCAGCAUCAUACCUUUCCGGGCUCUGAAGAGGCCGCUGCAGUUCCUCGGGCUCUUUGAGAACUCUCUGUGCCGCCUCACGCACAUUCCAGCCUACAAAGUAAGUGGUGACAAAAACGAAGAGCAGGUGCUGAAUGCCAUCGAGGCCUACACGGAGCACCGGCCUGAGAUCACCUCGCGGGCCAUCAACUUGCUUUUUGACAUCGCCCGCAUCGAGCGUUGCAACCAGCUGCUGCGGGCCCUGAAGCUGGUCAUCACGGCCCUCAAGUGCCACAAAUAUGACAGGAACAUUCAAGUGACAGGCAGCGCCGCUCUCUUCUACCUAACAAAUUCCGAGUACCGCUCAGAGCAGAGUGUGAAGCUGCGCCGGCAGGUUAUCCAGGUGGUGCUGAAUGGCAUGGAAUCCUACCAGGAGGUGACGGUGCAGCGGAACUGCUGCCUGACGCUCUGCAACUUCAGCAUCCCCGAGGAGCUGGAAUUCCAGUACCGCCGGGUCAACGAGCUCCUGCUCAGCAUCCUCAACCCCACGCGGCAGGACGAGUCUAUCCAGCGGAUCGCCGUGCACCUGUGCAAUGCCCUGGUCUGCCAGGUAGACAACGACCACAAGGAGGCCGUGGGCAAGAUGGGCUUUGUCGUGACCAUGCUGAAGCUGAUUCAGAAGAAGCUGCUGGACAAGACAUGUGACCAGGUCAUGGAGUUCUCCUGGAGUGCCCUGUGGAACAUCACAGAUGAAACUCCUGACAACUGCGAGAUGUUCCUCAAUUUCAACGGCAUGAAGCUCUUCCUGGACUGCCUGAAGGAAUUCCCAGAGAAGCAGGAACUGCAUAGGAAUAUGCUAGGACUUUUGGGGAAUGUGGCAGAAGUGAAGGAGCUGAGGCCUCAACUAAUGACUUCCCAGUUCAUCAGCGUCUUCAGCAACCUGUUGGAGAGCAAGGCCGAUGGGAUCGAGGUUUCCUACAAUGCCUGCGGCGUCCUCUCCCACAUCAUGUUUGAUGGACCCGAGGCCUGGGGCGUCUGUGAGCCCCAGCGUGAGGAGGUGGAGGAACGCAUGUGGGCUGCCAUCCAGAGCUGGGACAUAAACUCUCGGAGAAACAUCAAUUACAGGUCAUUUGAACCAAUUCUCCGCCUCCUUCCCCAGGGAAUCUCUCCUGUCAGCCAGCACUGGGCAACCUGGGCCCUGUAUAACCUCGUGUCUGUCUACCCGGACAAGUACUGCCCUCUGCUGAUCAAAGAAGGGGGGAUGCCCCUUCUGAGGGACAUAAUUAAGAUGGCGACCGCACGGCAGGAGACCAAGGAAAUGGCCCGCAAGGUGAUUGAGCACUGCAGUAACUUUAAAGAGGAGAACAUGGACACGUCUAGAUAGAGGCCUCCGUCCCCAUGGCCGCCACCGCUCUGGACCACAGGCGGGGAGGAAGCAUGCUCAAGCAGCCCAGCGGGCGGGCCCCUUCCGAGGGAGCCUCCCACGGAGUGAAGAGACAUGGGGGACUUUUGCACAACCGACGCUUUUCCUUAAUGUUAGUGAGAUAUAUAUAUAUUAUAUAUAUAUAUUUUUUUUUUGGUUAGGAAGUGUGAAGUUUUGUGUGUAUGAUUUCUGUGCAAAAACAAAAGCAACACUCCUGAGUCCUUGCAGCUUCCUUGGCCAUUCUCAAACCCACUCAGCCUUCAUCGCUGACACACACACUCCUACCCCAACCAGACUAAAUGCCUAUAACGCUGUGAGUGUCCAGUCCUUGUCCAGGAAACUCAGAUCCCGGCCUGGCUUCCUUUCAUGAGAGGAGCAGGCCUUGGACAGCGUAUCGAGCAUCCUGACCCACUGCCCCUGCCUGAGAACGCCAUCUCGGCUCCCGGGCACAGCUGAUGGGGUUUGGGGAUUAGAACUUACCCCACUGGGUCUCCCAAAAGCCUUGGUGCUCCCGGCUGUGGGCCAUCUGGGGCAGGAAAGUGAGCCAUUCCUAGGCUGAGGUCCAGGCAGCCCUGCCCCUGAAGACCCUCUAGGAGCAGGGCACCCAGUGGCCCUGCUGCUGUCCAGCCAGGCCUGCCUGAGGCCACGCUGCUAUGGAGGCUGCCUCCUAGUCUCCCACCAGGUCCCAGGCUGUGGAAAGCCCCAGCCCAGGGAUGGUCAGAACUCAGGGGCAGAUUCCACUGCCCCUUCUGCCAAACACAUCCAGAACCUGCCCUCAGCCCUGGAAGCUAGCAUCUUCUGGGGCCAGGGGCUUGCUUCCUCGCUCCAUAGCCCUCAACUGCCCAGGCGCUCCCACCAGCAGAACUGAGCCUGCCUCCUCCUCCCAGCCUGCCCCGCUGCCCAGAGGACCCCACGCCUCUCAGAGGCAGAGGUCCCAUGACAGCCUUUGACCCACAACGGCCACACAGCCGCCUCCAGACCAGCACUCGGACUGCCCUGCAGUGGCCGCUUGGGCCUCCCUGGCGGUCCCGCCCUGCCCUAGGCUUUACCUUGGAAGCCUGAGAGGCGCCGGCUCUCUUGCUCCUCCAUCGAUGGACACUGCAUUGCUUCUCAUCGGACACUUGUGGAGCGCAGGGGCCUGGGGAGCAGCGCUAACCCUGGAGGCAGCCUUUGGGUGAUGGCUUUUUCUUCCCUUUUCCUCCCGCGGGCCUGUUUUCAGGUGUUCCUAGCAUUUCUGCCUCCAGGCAGGACGGCAGGGGUGAGCAGCUUUGGGAGAGACACCUGGCCUUUUUCUCCUGGAGCCUCUCCCUCCCGGCCCUGGGAAGUGGGCGCAGCCCUGUGUUCCCCCAGCUUGGCAGAUGGGCUGCAUGCGGCGCUCCCUUCCUUCCCACGCUCAGCGGCCCCGGCCAGACCCUGGCAGACUUCACACCUCAUUGCUUUACCCCCUGGGGCCUGGGGAAAUGUCUGUACUUUGGGAAGUCACAGAAAUACAUUUUUGUGCAAAAUGGAAAA